GUUUGAUGAAACAGUUACAUGCUUUGCUGUCCAAGAUUUACUUCUCAACUUGGUUGAUCAGCCUGUAAAUGCUUGCUUUGGUUAUAAAGGGAAUUAGUGGAAAAAGAAUUUAAAGUGUAUGUCUUACUGUUAGGAUGGGGAAUGGCACUGAGAAUGUGUGCUGAGGUUGGGGGAGUACAUGAUAGUAAGGGCCAUGUGUGUUUCUGUGUGGGGGGAGAUUGUCUUCUUAAUAGGAAAAAAUGAUGUUUAUGAUAUGGUUUAAGAAACAAAAGUAUGUUCUAGUUUUAGAAAAAUUAGUAUGGGAUUUCAUUUCAAGCAAAAAAAGAUGAGUGCUCCUGUGGGAUAGACUAAAAUAGGCGUUUAAACCAGUUAACAAAGAAAGAUUAUGUAAUGUGUUACAUGGAAGAUGCAGUUUUUGUUAGUUGUCUCCCUCUCUUCUUCUGGAAUGGAGCCUUCCAGAGUUCUUGGGUCGUUCUGGAGUUUGUUGAGCAUUACCCUGUAUCUGCCUUAUCUUUGUUUUCUGAGUGGUAAGCUUAUGAGGGGUUUGGAGUCUUGGCUGAAACUUAAUAAUACAGGUUGAGUAUCCCUUAUGUGAAAUGUUUGGGACCAGAAGUGUUUCAGAUUUCAGAUUUUGGAAUAUUUACAUAUACAUAAUGAGAUACCUUGGGGAUGGGAUCCAAGUCUAAACAUGAAAUUCACUUAUGUUUCAUAUACACAUAGCCUGAAGGUAAUUUUAUACAACAUUUUAAGUAAUUUUGUGCAUGAAACAAGGUUUGUGUUAAGUACUUAUGUGUGGAAUUUUCCACUUGUGGUGUCAUGUCAGCGCUCAAAAAAGCUUUGGAUUUUGGAGCAUUGAAGAUUUUGGAUUUUUGAAUUGGGGAUGCUCACCUUUAUUAGAAAUACAGCAUUGACUAAAAUAGACAUGGCCAUUGUGCUUUGAGCAGAAGCUGGAGAGACUUGGAGAGGGCCAGACUAGUGGUAGUAGGCUCUUGUAAGUCAAAUUAAGAAGCUCUUACUUUAGGGCAAUGGGAAGGUGUUAAAGAGUUUAAAAAUAGGAAUAGGAUAAUUUUAUUUUGCAUUAUUCUCUGGCCAUAAUGUGGGAAAUGGCUUCCUAGGAAUAUGCCUGGAGGUGUGCCUAACAGUUGGGAGGUUGUUGUAGUAGUUCCCAGCUAUUAGGUAGUAGUGACUUGGACUAGAAAGGUGGUAAGGGAUUGAUGAGAAGUAGAUCAAUUUAUAAAAGACAAAGGAGGAGUAAUUGAUGAAACUUGAUGGUUUAUUGAAUAUGGAAAUUGAGGAAAAGGAAGAAGUCAAUGGUGAUACUCAAAUUUCUGACAUACGCAUCUAUGUUAAUGGAGGCCCCAUUUUCUAAGGUGGUGUGAUGCUUUGCUGUUGCUGCUGGAACAAAGUACCACAAACUUAGUGACUUAAAACAACACAAAUCUCAAGCCUGAAGUGAAUCUUAACUGGGCUAAAAGCAAAGUGUGGCAGGGCCAUGUGCCUUUCUGGAGGCUCCAGGGGAAAAUCAUUGUCUUGCCUUUUCCAGCUUCUAGAGGCAGUGCACAUUCCUUGGCUUCUAGCCAUCUUCCAUCUUCAAACCUGGCAAUGGCCCAUUGAGUCUUUCUCAUCCUGCAUCACUAUGACAUUAACUAACCUGCUUUUCUCUUUCAUUAAUAACGGGCCUUGUGAUUACAUUAGGUCCACCCAGAUAAGCCUGGAUUCUCUCCCCACUGCAAGGUCAGCUGAUUAACAAUCUUAUUUCCAUCUAUAAUCUUAAUCCCCCCUUUCCAUGUAACAUAACAUAAUUGUGGCACUGGGGGAUUAUUAGAGGGCCAUUAAUCUCCUCACAGCAGAUAAGAACACGUUUUACAGAGGAAAUAAAUUUAGUUUUAGAGAUGCAUUCAAGUGGGGAUGACAAAUAAACAGUUGGUUUUUGAGCUUGGGAUAAAGAUAUAGAUAUGACAAAAGCCUAUACAUGAAAAUUGAAGCCAUAGAAUGAAUGUUUGUUUCUUAGGUGGGGAGGGAAUACGUGAAAUGACAAGAAGGCCCGGGCCAGUGUCCUUAGGGUUUGGGUAAAGUUGCAGGUAGUGAGAUUGAGAAGGAGCCACUGGAGGGUAGGAGGAAAUCUAGAGGAAUUUGAUUUUAAGGAGGUUGGUAAUGACCUUUAUAGACUAUUGUGUGUUUGGUCUGAAAGGAUACUUAAACAUCUUUUUAAGCCUAUUGCUAUUACAGAUCAGGAAAUUGAGGCCCAGAGAGAUGAAGUCACUUGUCUAAGAUUGUAUAACUAGUUAAUAGAAGUGCUUCUUCAUUCCUACUUAGUUUAUUUGCCACCCUGCAACCCAGGUCCAUUAAAUCUUUUCAUUUUGAAGAUAGUGUUAGGAAAAGAUUUGGCUCUGUGUGUGUGUGUGUGUGUGUGUGUGUGUGUGUGUCUGUGUGUUUCAUUGAUAUUCUGAAUACUGAGAGCAAAUUGCUGGAAUGAUGUCUGACUGGUGCCUUAUUUACAUGCAAGUUAAAAAUUGUUUAUACUAAAUAAUAGAAUUAAUAAUUACUUUUUAAAUCAUGUAAACUUUUUUAAAUGCAACUUCAUCUCUUUUUGCAGUUUCUUUCACCUCAUUUUGCAAUCUCUCUCUAUCCUUUUUAUUUUUUCAAUAAGUUUUUUAUUUUGGAAUGAUGUUAGAUUUACCAAAGUUGUAGAUAGUGGAGUUCCCAUAUACCCAUACCCUCACACAGUUCCCUCAGUUGUUAAGAAGAUCUUAUACUACCAUGGUACAUUUGUCAAAACUAAGGAACAACUCUGGUACAUUCCUGUUGACUAAACUAAAUAGUAAGCUCCAGACUUUAUUUGGAUUUCACUGAUAUCCUUUUAAAGAACGUUGUCUGGGAUCCAAUCCAGGAUAUCACAUUGCAUUUAAUCAUCAUCUUCGUAGACGCUUCUUAGUUGGUUUCGCUUUUUUUUUUCUUGUAAUCCUGACAGUUUUGAGGAAUCCUGCUUAGGUGUUUUGUAGAAUGUCUCUCAGCUGGAGUUUGUCUGAUGUCUUAUUAUGAUUAGAUUUGCGUUACAGGUUUUUGGGAAGAAGAGCACAGAGGUCAAGGGCCCUUCUCAUCACGUCAUAUCAAAGCUAGUGCAAGUCAUCAACAUGACCAGUAAUGUCAACCUUGAUCACCUGGCCCUAGUAGUGUUUGUCAAGUUUCUUUACUGGAAAGCUGAAGUGAGUAGUGAAUAUAGUAUGGACAAGGCAAUGGUUGAAUUUGCUACAUUGGAUCGGCAACUAAACCAUUAUGUAAAGGCUGUUCAAUCUACAAUAAAUCAUGUGAAAGAAGAACGUCCAGAAAAAAUACCAGAUUUAAAAUUAUUGGUAGAGAAGAAAUUUUUGGCUUUACAGAGCAAGAAUUCUGAUGCAGACUUUCAAAAUAAUGAAAAAUUUGUACAGUUUAAACAACAGCUGAAAGAACUAAAGAAGCAAUGUGGUCUUCAAGCUGACAGAGAAGCUGACGGAACAGAAGGAGUGGAUGAAGAUAUAAUUGUGACCCAAAGUCAGACCAACUUCACCUGCCCCAUUACAAAGGAGGAAAUGAAGAAGCCAGUGAAAAAUAAAGUGUGUGGCCACACCUAUGAAGAGGACGCCAUUGUUCGCAUGAUUGAGUCCAGGCAAAAGCGGAAGAAAAAGGCCUACGAAAUGCUCUGCCCGGGUAGUGCCUGGAGGUGGGGACCCAGCCGCUCCUGCGAGGCCUGAAGGGCUGACUCCUGCACAGCGAUGAUGCGGCAGCUGAAGAUCGGGUAUUGCCACACUGAACUCGCUCACCAAGAUGUCGUGGGAUUAAUGCCGAAUGCUUACGGAGACAGUUGUUUCUCCAGAGGAGGCAUGCCUUGAUUCAGCACUGUGGCAUGAUGGCCUUCUCUUAUCCUUUCUGCUUUAAAAACUUGUGUUUAUUGGAGACGAAGGAGAAACAAGGUCCUUCCCAGUUCCAGCAUCAACCUCGCCUCCAGGAAGUCUUCCCUGAGCCCUUAUUCAUGCUGGACAAAAUGUCGUUAGCACCCCAUGUCAUGCCAACAUUGUCAGUGCAGCUGGCUCCUCUCCACGAGCUUCUUGAGAGCGGAAGCUGUGGACUAGGGCAGGGACUGGUGCACGGCAGGACCUGAAGUGAACUCCCCAGUCCUUGACACACAUCAGCCUGCUUAUUUCUCAGCCUUAUUGGACAGGCUUGUCCUCUGCCUUCAUGUUCUUAAAGGGAAAAACUGAGGCACAGAGAAUUUAGUCACUUACCCAGAGUGACACAGCCAGGGGGUUUAAGCCCAGGUCUUUCUCAUUCUUGAGCCUGCAAUUCUGUCAGUAGGCCAUCCAGCUCCCCUUGGGAGGGCUAUUUGGUUCAUGCCUCUACCAUCAGAGUCUAUCUCCUCAGUGAACUCAGACCUUGUUUGACAUGGCUCACUCUGGGAUCCAUCCCACUGAAGUGAAGGUGGGCGCCUGCUCUGCAGCUGAGUGUGUGGUUAAGUCCAUCAGACAUUCUCAGCAUGCUCUCAUGCACUGACUAAAACCAUGAUGUCAUCAGGAAGUCCUCCCCACCUCACUCUCCACUUCCCUCUCCACUGCUUAUUCACUGUCUGGCUAUGAAAGUUAAGGCCUUUGCUGGGUAGAAUGGAAGAGACCAAGGCCAGGCAGUCCAAAGCAGAUAUUCAGGGUUAUGUUUUAAGGGAGGGUCAUCCCAGCAACCUACUUGGAGUUGCAUUUCAAUGUCAUGGAAGCCAAAGUUAUGAUACUUGGCUUUUCUAGUCACAAAAGUGUCUGUAUCCUCUUCAUGAUCUUAGCUGCUUUUUUUCAUACUUACAGACAUAAUUCACCAGGCACGGUGGCUCAUGCCUGUAAUCCCAGCACUUUGGGAGGCCAAGGCAGGUGGAUCACUUGAGC